GCACUCACCGCCUUCCUGGUGGACGGGCUCCUGGUGGCUGUGCUGCUGCUGUGAGCGGGCCCCUGCUCCUCCAUGCCCCCAGCUCUCCGGCUGGGUGGGCUUGGCCAUGGUCAGCGUGAACGCGCCCCUCGGGGCUCCAGUGGAGAGUUCUUACGGUGUCACCGAGGCCCUCCAACCUGCCCUUCCAGCCAGCAGUGGAGGACAGGCUCCCAGGCCUCCCAAGUCUCAGGCUUUUCUUCCUCUGCCCUCACUCUCUGCCUUCUACAUCAAGACUUUACUUCCCCAGAUUGAUUGGCAGCCCUUGAAAAUGUCUGCACAGAAGGCAAUGAGGGCUGGAGGGAGUGAGAAGAACAGAGUGCACCAUGAGCUUCAGACAGCCAGGACCAGCUGUGUAAUUUUCAGGGCCCCGUCCAAAACAAAAAUGCACAAUCCCUUGUUCAAAAGUCAUGAUGAAUUUUAGGACAACCACAGCAGAGCACUGAACCAGGAACCAGGACUUUCUAAGGGUUGGGUUGCCUGUGACUGCACUGGCGAUACCCCCACAAAGCCCACUCUGAAGGUAGGAGACGGGUGGAGAGAAACAGGGGGAUGGCAAGGGGGAUACGAAACAGGGAGAGGGAGGAGGGGGAAGAGGAUGGACGUCUACCAGGCCCCACUUGGUGCUUGAUUUAUGCCAUCUCAUUUCCUUCUCAAACCACCCUUUGAAGUUGAUUGUACAUUUUACAGAAAAGGAAACUGAGGCUCGGAGAGGAGAAUCAUUUACCCAAGGUCCCAGUUAGUAGACGGUAGGUGCCUGAAUGUAAAUCCAGGUCUCUGCCUGCUCCGGGAGGGGGUGGGGGUGAGGGAAACAGGAGAAUGUGAUGGGAAAAUCCGAGAUGGAGCCAGCCUGGGCCAGAAACACUGGGAGCUGUGGGAGACGGAGAGGGGCAGGGUGGGAUCACAGGGAGCAGGAGCGGGGAAUUGGAGGUGAAUCUGGCCCUCCCAAACUUCCAGUCCAUUCUGCUCCCAGGGGAACCGGGAAACUGCGGGGGAACUGGAAGGGAGCUCCCAGAACAAGGAUCCAGAAGAUUGGCAUCUGGGGCCUGGGAUUUAGGUUUCUAAAUCGUGGGCCAUGGGGCAGCCUUAUCUCUGCAAAAGCAUUGAGGGUAGAAGUCAAUGAUUUGGGAAGUUAUUGAAUUAGGGGAUCUCGGAGGUAGGCUGUCAGUGCCUGAUAGUAUCAGUUAGAAUGCCUGACUUGGGGUGACAAUGGCUUGGAGGGGUGGGUGAGUCAAGGGUCAAAUGAGUGCCCGUGAGUCAUGAUGCCUGCCUUGUACAAUUGAUAACUGAACAUCGGUGAGUUAGGGCCCCAGCAGUUGUAAUUAGCACCCCGGGUGUCAGCCAGAAACCAACAAACAGCCAAAUCCCUGCAGCCCCGCCCAGCCUAUCCACCGGCGGGGGACCGAUUAACCAUUAACCCCCACCCCUCCCCGGCAGAGCCUCCACCCCUUCACAGAGGCUAGGCCAAGACUCCCAGCAGAUCUUCCCAGAGGACGGUUUGAAAGGAAGGCAGAGAGGGCACUGGGAGGAGGCAGUGGGAGGGCGGAGGGCGGGGGCCUUCGGGGUGGGCGCCCAGGGUAGGGCAGGUGGCCGCGGCGUGGAGGCAGGGAGAAUGCGACUCUCCAAAACCCUCGUCGACAUGGACAUGGCCGACUACAGUGCUGCACUGGACCCAGCCUACACCACCCUGGAAUUUGAGAAUGUGCAGGUGUUGACGAUGGGCAAUGACACGUCCCCAUCAGAAGGCACCAACCUCAACGCGCCCAACAGCCUGGGUGUCAGCGCCCUGUGUGCCAUCUGCGGGGACCGGGCCACGGGCAAACACUACGGUGCCUCGAGCUGUGACGGCUGCAAGGGCUUCUUCCGGAGGAGCGUGCGGAAGAACCACAUGUACUCCUGCAGAUUUAGCCGGCAGUGCGUGGUGGACAAAGACAAGAGGAACCAGUGCCGCUACUGCAGGCUCAAGAAAUGCUUCCGGGCUGGCAUGAAGAAGGAAGCCGUCCAGAAUGAGCGGGACCGGAUCAGCACUCGAAGGUCAAGCUAUGAGGACAGCAGCCUGCCCUCCAUCAAUGCGCUCCUGCAGGCGGAGGUCCUGUCCCGACAGAUCACCUCCCCCGUCUCCGGGAUCAACGGCGACAUUCGGGCGAAGAAGAUUGCCAGCAUCGCAGAUGUGUGUGAGUCCAUGAAGGAGCAGCUGCUGGUUCUCGUUGAGUGGGCCAAGUACAUCCCAGCUUUCUGCGAGCUCCCCCUGGACGACCAGGUGGCCCUGCUCAGAGCCCAUGCUGGCGAGCACCUGCUGCUCGGAGCCACCAAGAGAUCCAUGGUGUUCAAGGACGUGCUGCUCCUAGGCAAUGACUACAUUGUCCCUCGGCACUGCCCGGAGCUGGCGGAGAUGAGCCGGGUGUCCAUACGCAUCCUUGACGAGCUGGUGCUGCCCUUCCAGGAGCUGCAGAUCGAUGACAAUGAGUAUGCCUACCUCAAAGCCAUCAUCUUCUUUGACCCAGAUGCCAAGGGGCUGAGCGAUCCAGGGAAGAUCAAGCGGCUGCGUUCCCAGGUGCAGGUGAGCUUGGAGGACUACAUCAACGACCGCCAGUAUGACUCGCGUGGCCGCUUUGGAGAGCUGCUGCUGCUGCUGCCCACCUUGCAGAGCAUCACCUGGCAGAUGAUCGAGCAGAUCCAGUUCAUCAAGCUCUUCGGCAUGGCCAAGAUUGACAACCUGUUGCAGGAGAUGCUGCUGGGAGGGUCCCCCAGCGAUGCACCCCAUGCCCACCACCCCCUGCACCCUCACCUGAUGCAGGAACAUAUGGGAACCAACGUCAUCGUUGCCAACACAAUGCCCACUCACCUCAGCAACGGACAGAUGUCCACCCCUGAGACCCCACAGCCCUCACCGCCAGGUGGCUCAGGGUCUGAGCCCUAUAAGCUCCUGCCGGGAGCCGUCGCCACAAUCGUCAAGCCCCUCUCUGCCAUCCCCCAGCCGACCAUCACCAAGCAGGAAGUUAUCUAGCAAGCCGCUGGGGCUUGGGGGCUCCACUGGCUCCCCCCAGCCCCCUAAGAGAGCACCUGGUGAUCACGUGGUCACGGCAAAGGAAGACGUGAUGCCAGGACCAGUCCCAGAGCAGGAAUGGGAAGGAUGAAGGGCCCGAGAACAUGGCCUAAGGGCCACAUCCCACUGCCACCCUUGACGCCCUGCUCUGGAUAACAAGACUUUGACUUGGGGAGACCUCUACUGCCUUGGACAACUUUUCUCAUGUUGAAGCCACUGCCUUCACCUUCACCUUCAUCCAUGUCCAACCCCCGACUUCAUCCCAAAGGACAGCCGCCUGGAGAUGACUUGAGGCCUUACUUAAACCCAGCUCCCUUCUUCCCUAGCCUGGUGCUUCUCCUCUCCUAGCCCCUGUCAUGGUGUCCAGACAGAGCCCUGUGAGGCUGGGUCCAAUUGUGGCACUUGGGGCACCUUGCUCCUCCUUCUGCUGCUGCCCCCACCUCUGCUGCCUCCCUCUGCUGUCACCUUGCUCAGCCAUCCCGUCUUCUCCAACACCACCUCUCCAGAGGCCAAGGAGGCCUUGGAAACGAUUCCCCCAGUCAUUCUGGGAACAUGUUGUAAGCACUGACUGGGACCAGGCACCAGGCAGGGUCUAGAAGGCUGUGGUGAGGGAAGACGCCUUUCUCCUCCAACCCAACCUCAUCCUCCUUCUUCAGGGACUUGGGUGGGUACUUGGGUGAGGAUCCCUGAAGGCCUUCAACCCGAGAAAACAAACCCAGGUUGGCGACUGCAACAGGAACUUGGAGUGGAGAGGAAAAGCAUCAGAAAGAGGCAGACCAUCCACCAGGCCUUUGAGAAAGGGUAGAAUUCUGGCUGGUAGAGCAGGUGAGAUGGGACAUUCCAAAGAACAGCCUGAGCCAAGGCCUAGUGGUAGUAAGAAUCUAGCAAGAAUUGAGGAAGAAUGGUGUGGGAGAGGGAUGAUGAAGAGAGAGAGGGCCUGCUGGAGAGCAUAGGGUCUGGAACACCAGGCUGAGGUCCUGAUCAGCUUCAAGGAGUAUGCAGGGAGCUGGGCUUCCAGAAAAUGAACACAGCAGUUCUGCAGAGGACGGGAGGCUGGAAGCUGGGAGGUCAGGUGGGGUGGAUGAUAUAAUGCGGGUGAGAGUAAUGAGGCUUGGGGCUGGAGAGGACAAGAUGGGUAAACCCUCACAUCAGAGUGACAUCCAGGAGGAAUAAGCUCCCAGGGCCUGUCUCAAGCUCUUCCUUACUCCCAGGCACUGUCUUAAGGCAUCUGACAUGCAUCAUCUCAUUUAAUCCUCCCUUCCUCCCUAUUAACCUAGAGAUUGUUUUUGUUUUUUAUUCUCCUCCUCCCUCCCCGCCCUCACCCGCCCCACUCCCUCCUAACCUAGAGAUUGUUACAGAAGCUGAAAUUGCGUUCUAAGAGGUGAAGUGAUUUUUUUUCUGAAACUCACACAACUAGGAAGUGGCUGAGUCAGGACUUGAACCCAGGUCUCCCUGGAUCAGAACAGGAGCUCUUAACUACAGUGGCUGAAUAGCUUCUCCAAAGGCUCCCUGUGUUCUCACCGUGAUCAAGUUGAGGGGCUUCCGGCUCCCUUCUACAGCCUCAGAAACCAGACUCGUUCUUCUGGGAACCCUGCCCACUCCCAGGACCAAGAUUGGCCUGAGGCUGCACUAAAAUUCACUUAGGGUCGAGCAUCCUGUUUGCUGAUAAAUAUUAAGGAGAAUUCAUGACUCUUGACAGCUUUUCUCUCUUCACUCCCCAAGUCAAGGGGAGGGGUGGCAGGGGUCUGUUUCCUGGAAGUCAGGCUCAUCUGGCCUGUUGGCAUGGGGGUGGGACAGUGUGCACAGUGUGGGGGCAGGGGAGGGCUAAGCAGGCCUGGGUUUGAGGGCUGCUCCGGAGACCGUCACUCCAGGUGCAUUCUGGAAGCAUUAGACCCCAGGAUGGAGCGACCAGCAUGUCAUCCAUGUGGAAUCUUGGUGGCUUUGAGGACAUUCUGGAAAAUGCCACUGACCAGUGUGAACAAAAGGGAUGUGUUAUGGGGCUGGAGGUGUGAUUAGGUAGGAGGGAAACUGUUGGACCGACUCCUGCCCCCUGCUCAACACUGACCCCUCUGAGUGGUUGGAGGCAGUGCCCCAGUGCCCAGAAAUCCCACCAUUAGUGAUUGUUUUUUAUGAGAAAGAGGCGUGGAGAAGUAUUGGGGCAAUGUGUCAGGGAGGAAUCACCACAUCCCUACGGCAGUCCCAGCCAAGCCCCCAAUCCCAGCGGAGACUGUGCCCUGCUCAGAGCUCCCAAGCCUUCCCCCACCACCUCACUCAAGUGCCCCUGAAAUCCCUGCCAGACGGCUCAGCCUGGUCUGCGGUAAGGCAGGGAGGCUGGAACCAUUUCUGGGCAUUGUGGUCAUUCCCACUGUGUUCCUCCACCUCCUCCCUCCAGCGUUGCUCAGACCUCUGUCUUGGGAGAAAGGUUGAGAUAAGAAUGUCCCAUGGAGUGCCGUGGGCAACAGUGGCCCUUCAUGGGAACAAUCUGUUGGAGCAGGGGGUCAGUUCUCUGCUGGGAAUCUACCCCUUUCUGGAGGAGAAACCCAUUCCACCUUAAUAACUUUAUUGUAAUGUGAGAAACACAAAACAAAGUUUACUUUUUUGACUCUAAGCUGACAUGAUAUUAGAAAAUCUCUCGCUCUCUUUUUUUUUUUUUUUUUUUUUUUUGGCUACUUGAGUUGUGGUCCUAAAACAUAAAAUCUGAUGGACAAACAGAGGGUUGCUGGGGGGACAAGCGUGGGCACAAUUUCCCCACCAAGACACCCUGAUCUUCAGGCGGGUCUCAGGAGCUUCUAAAAAUCCGCAUGGCUCUCCUGAGAGUGGACAGAGGAGAGGAGAGGGUCAGAAAUGAACGCUCUUCUAUUUCUUGUCAUUACCAAGCCAAUUACUUUUGCCAAAUUUUUCUGUGAUCUGCCCUGAUUAAGAUGAAUUGUGAAAUUUACAUCAAGCAAUUAUCAAAGCGGGCUGGGUCCCAUCAGAACGACCCACAUCUUUCUGUGGGUGUGAAUGUCAUUAGGUCUUGCGCUGACCCCUGAGCCCCCAUCACUGCCGCCUGAUGGGGCAAAGAAACAAAAAACAUUUCUUACUCUUCUGUGUUUUAACAAAAGUUUAUAAAACAAAAUAAAUGGCGCAUAUGUUUUCUAAGUCCUUGGAUAAGUAUCUUUUCUUUCAGGUAUCAGAAAUAAGACUGAAUCUUCUGGUUCUACUUGGGGGUUAAAAAAUUUUUUUUAAAGGAAGAAUGAGAAUAGUUUUAUAGUUCUUUGUGAUGUGCAGAAUGUUUUUGUGUCCAUUAUAAUUUUUCAGUCUUCACAUCAAGAGGUAAGCAGUUAGACAUGAUUACUCCCACUUUCCAGAUGAGGAGACUGAGGCUUGGGGGAAGUGACUUCUCUUGGAAGGCAGAGGUGGACAUCUAACCCUGGUCUCUUGAUUCCAAGUACUUAGUAUAUCGAGAGAGUGAAAGUUGAUCCCCCUUCUUGAAGAGGGGAGUGAUGAGGGGAGAGUGCAAUGGCAAGAUCUGGAAGAAUGGCAAGAGGGUCCAAGGGUCUGUCAUCCUCCACCAAGGUUCAAGACAGAACCUUUUGCUGGGUCACCUCAAUCUGCCAGCAAUGGAAGAUGAGUAGCUGUGGGGACAUUUCAUAAAAGCAAGUGGUUUUUUUGUUUUGUUUUGUUUUGUUUUUUGUUUUUUUUUCUAGAACAAGGCUGUGCACAGUGGCUCACCUCUGUAAUCCCAGCACUUUGGGAGGCUGAGGCGGGAGGAUCACUUGAGCUCAGGAGUUCGAGACCAGCCAGAGCAAUAUAAGGAGACCCCAUCUCUACAAAAAAUUUAAAAAUUAGCCAGGUAUAGUGGUGUGUGCCUAUAGUACCAGCUACUCUGAAGGCUGAGGUGGGAAGAUUGCUUCAGCCCAGGAGUUCGAGGAUGCAGUGAGCUAUGAAUGCAACACUGCACUACAGCCUGGAUGAAAGAACAAGACUCUGUCUCAAAACAUAAAUAAUAAGUAAAAAGAAUAAAAGCAAGAGAUGCACUUGAGAAUCUCCAGCCAGAUCUGUAGCCACUGGGCUUCUCUCCAAGGCUAAACUAUUACAGGAGGGUGGCCUUGUGUCUCGGUCACCACAGACCACAGCGUUCCAUUCACUCGGGGUUGUGCUGGAGCUGGCUUGUGAGAACUGACUGUUAGCUUCUCUUCCCAACUCCAUGUUUGCCAGUGCCACACUGAUAGCUUGAAAUUGGUUAUUGCCGGAGUGUUUACACCACAAGGACUAGCAAACUCUACAAAUCCGGGCUUUUGUUCCUGGAGAGCCCGUUGUUAACAUUCACCAGCACACCACAGCAUUCGGCAAUGGCUGGACCAUGGGAUGCCUACAUAUGGGGACAUCCUCCUUGGGGAUGAGGGUAGAGCAGGGCGAUCCUUUCACCUCUUCCUUAAGGGAGGGGACAAAAGUUCUGGUCUGGGAAGCACACGUUUUGCUGAUCAGCGUAACCUUGGGCAGGUCACUCCACCACUCCGAGCCUCAUCUGUAAAGUGGGAAUGAUAUCUCCCUCCAGGGCAGAUGUCAGGAUUCAAUGGAAUGAGAUCACAGUAACUGUGAGAGCUCCCGUUACAUGAGGAGUACAAGUGAACUCUUCAUGCGCCCCUUUUUAGCGAGAAGUUAACCAUUAAACUCUCCAGGCUUCAGAGCACCCAUUCGCUGUCUACCUGAUCCCUAGGGCCGCUCCCGCCUUCCCCUGUGCCUUCCCUCCACUAGUCAGCACCAGGAAAUGUUUUCGAUAACGUUGCAACGGAGGCCUUGUUCAUGCUGCCGCCAUCGGGGACAAGCGCGGGGGGGGGGGGGUGGAGGCCAGAGGAGACUAUUUCAGUCCUAAAUUGUGCUUAAUAAACCCAUAUCAAAACCAUAAA